AGUGGCCUCGAGACCCUGCCUGCCUGAGGAGGCCUCGGUUGGAUGCGAAGGAGCUGCAGCAUCCAGGUACGCUGCCGGCUAGGGCCGAGCAGGGGCUGCCAGUCCCACUGCCUGCGCGCCCACCUGGGCCAGUCUCCGCUUGCCGCGUCCUCCCAUCCCCUAGUCUGCAGGCCUGGUGCCCUUGAAUUCACCCGCUUCUGUUGCGUUGCGGACCGCGAGCUGCACUGCUUCCUGCCCAAGCCCAAGCUCCUCGCAGCAGUAGGGGACAAGAUGCCAACUGGCAAGCAGCUAGCUGACAUUGGCUAUAAGACCUUCUCUACCUCCAUGAUGCUUCUCACUGUGUAUGGGGGGUACCUCUGCAGUGUCCGAGUCUACCACUAUUUCCAGUGGCGCAGGGCCCAGCGCCAGGCCGCAGAAGAACAGAAGACCUCAGGAAUCAUGUAGAACUGGGGGGCUUUUUCUCCUGAGCAGAGAGGCCCAAGGCAUGCUGUGGAGAGACUUCACCUGCCACCAUUUCCAGGUCAACAGGACUAGAGCGUUGAUGGUUUUCAAACCCUGUUGGAAGAAAGUGCCCAUGGUUUCUCUGGUUCUGCCAGUUUGACAGUUUAUGGAGGCUUUUGAAUCGUAAUAGCAAUGUGAGGGUGAGGUACACCUACAGACAUUAAAUAAUUUGCUGUGUC